GUUACCCUAGCAACGGAGAGACGCCACGCUCUGCACAGUCUAUUUUCGGAGCCUAGCCAGAGACGGGAAAACUGACCAAGGCACGAUUUAUCCUGGCCUAGCAUGCCUUGGUUAGGAAAUGUUUUGGGGGAUAUCACACUUCAGACUGAAAAAAAAAUGGCCCCAGUACUUACUACGUGAAUAAUGUCCUUUGUGCGACAACUUGAACGCUGUGGUCUGAGGGUUCCAGUGUUGCUUGGUUAGAUAAGCUGAGGAGUGAGAAGUAAUCAGACCUUCACUUGGUGGGCCCGAGUGUACUGUGCAGAGACUACUUGUACCUACAAGACCUGCUACUCGCCAAGGGCUGAUUGGGAGAAUAAUGGAAUCUGAAAAUAUGGAUUCUGAAAAUAUGAAGACAGAAAAUAUGGAAUCUCAAAAUGUAGACUUUGAGAGUGUUUCUUCAGUUACAGCUCUGGAAGCCCUCUCUAAGCUACUUAAUCCUGAAGAAGAGGAUGAUUCUGACUAUGGACAGACAAAUGGUUUAUCUACUAUUGGAGCCAUGGGUCCUGGGAAUAUUGGACCACCCCAAAUAGAAGAGCUCAAAGUCAUCCCUGAAACCAGCGAGGAAAAUAAUGAGGACAUCUGGAAUUCAGAAGAGAUUCCAGAAGGAGCAGAAUAUGAUGAUAUGUGGGAUGUUAGAGAAAUCCCAGAGUAUGAGAUUAUAUUCAGACAGCAGGUGGGAACUGAAGAUAUAUUUUUAGGGUUGUCAAAAAAGGACUCCUCAACAGGUUGUUGCAGUGAACUAGUGGCUAAAAUUAAAUUGCCAAAUACAAACCCUUCUGAUAUUCAAAUUGAUAUCCAGGAAACAAUCCUUGACCUUCGUACUCCUCAGAAGAAGCUGUUGAUAACUCUUCCUGAGCUGGUGGAAUGUACCAGUGCCAAAGCAUUCUAUAUCCCAGAGACUGAAACUCUUGAAAUCACUAUGACUAUGAAAAGAGAGUUAGAUAUUGCUAAUUUCUUCUGAAACUGCAUGAAAAAGAUAAAAAGUAGUAAAAUGGCAUUGGUAACAAUUAAAAAACUUUGAAAAAAAUGAUUGUUUUCUAUAUUCUCUUUAUUAUUCUGACAUAUUUUUGAAAGGGACAAAAUUCAGUUCUAGUGAUAUUGUGACCAUUUACAGUAAUUUCUAUUACUCUGUUAGGAAAUAUGUUUCCUUGGCCAGGUGCAAUGGCUCAUGCCUGUAAUCCCAACACUUUGGGAGGCCGAAGCAGGCGGAUCACUUGAGGUCAGGAGUUUGAGACCAGCCUGGUCAACAUGGCGAAACCCUGUCUCUACUAAAAAUACGAAAAUUAGCCUGGCGUGGUGGCAGGUGCCUGUAAUCCCAGCUACUCUGUCUCAAAAAACAAACAAAAAAAGGAAAUAUGUUUUCUUAUGUAAAUAAACUAUUCUAUUUUUAUAGUGAUAGCUGAGUAGAAUCUUUACAGGUUAAAAAAUUAGAAUAUUUCAUGGUCAAUUACAUAAUUGAAAUAUGAUCAUGAAAUGGUUGGUCCACUUACUUCAGUAGUCUGAAAAACUUAUGCUAAUUAUUUACAUUUACACUGUGAUACAAUCAGUUGCAUAGCAAUUGGUCAUUAUUAUUACCAGAGAAUUUUAUUUGGUUGCUUUUUCAUUGAUUUGAGCAAAUGAUUUACAGUGUUCUCUGUUUAGGCUCUCACUGUUGUUCUGGAAUAUACAGGUAAUAAAUAGUUUGAUGUACCAUACUAUCAACAUAUUUACUUGAGUAAGGAACACUUUUGUGCGUACAGUAUUAUUUGGCUUCUUCAGUUGUGCUUUUAAUGCUUGGAUAUAGUUAGGUUAAAAACAUUUUUUAUAUGCACUAAUAAUUAUUAGCAUUGCCUUUUUGGGUACUGUAUUUAUAUGUAGUCAAUUGAAAUCCUUGACUUUAAAAUAAAUUUAAAGUGUGGCACAUUUACAAA